AGAGCAUCUUUUGGGGGGAGGGAAUUCAGCGGAUCAGUCUUAAGAGGAGCUUUUUUUUGGAGCGAGAAAUCAUAUAAAAUAAAAUGAAAUAAAACAAGGAGGAAGGCAACCAGCUGUUAGGGGAAAAAUAAGGCAGAUAAAGGAGCGGGGAGAGAAAUUAAUUGCCAACCAGGAGGAGUUGGGCUGUAUUUUUCAAAGGUGGGGAGAGUGGAGCACACACCUUGAGGAGGAAAGCGAGAAAGAAAAGAAAAAAGCAAGUGGAAAGGGGGGCUCGCCCAAGAAGGGUGAAGAAGCGAAGAAAGUCGAGGCGCCGAGGCUCCCAAAGCUGGCAGCUCCGGGUGGCGGUGCAGGGGCGAAGGGGGGGCGGGGGGAACCGUCGGACAUGCGGCUCUGGAGUUGGGUGCUGCACCUGGGGCUGCUGAGCGCCGCGCUGGGCUGCGGGCUGGCCGAGCGUCCCCGCCGGGCCCGGAGAGACCCGCGGGCCGGCCGACCCCCGCGCCCCGCCGCCGGCCCGGCCACCUGCGCCACCCGGGCGGCCCGCGGCCGCCGCGCCUCGCCGCCGCCGCCGCCGCCGCCGGGCGGUGCCUGGGAAGCCGUGCGCGUCCCCCGGCGGCGGCAGCAGCGGGAGGCGAGGGGCGCCACCGAGGAGCCGAGCCCGCCGAGCCGGGCGCUCUAUUUCAGCGGGCGAGGCGAGCAGCUGCGCCUCCGGGCCGACCUCGAGCUGCCCCGGGACGCGUUCACGCUGCAAGUGUGGCUGCGAGCGGAGGGGGGCCAGAGGUCUCCGGCAGUGAUCACAGGGCUGUAUGACAAAUGUUCUUAUAUCUCACGUGACCGAGGAUGGGUCGUGGGCAUUCACACCAUCAGUGACCAAGACAACAAAGACCCACGCUACUUUUUCUCCUUGAAGACAGACCGAGCCCGGCAAGUGACCACCAUCAAUGCCCACCGCAGCUACCUCCCAGGCCAGUGGGUAUACCUAGCUGCCACCUAUGAUGGGCAGUUCAUGAAGCUCUAUGUGAAUGGUGCCCAGGUGGCCACCUCUGGGGAACAAGUGGGUGGCAUAUUCAGCCCACUGACCCAGAAGUGCAAAGUGCUCAUGUUAGGGGGCAGUGCCCUGAAUCACAACUACCGGGGCUACAUCGAGCACUUCAGUCUGUGGAAGGUGGCCAGGACUCAGCGGGAGAUACUGUCUGACAUGGAAACCCAUGGCGCCCACACUGCUCUACCUCAGCUCCUCCUCCAGGAGAACUGGGACAAUGUGAAGCAUGCCUGGUCCCCCAUGAAGGAUGGCAGCAGCCCCAAAGUGGAAUUCAGCAAUGCCCACGGCUUUCUGCUGGACACGAGUCUGGAGCCUCCUCUGUGCGGACAGACAUUGUGUGACAACACAGAGGUCAUUGCCAGCUACAAUCAGCUCUCAAGUUUCCGCCAGCCCAAGGUGGUGCGCUACCGCGUGGUCAACCUCUAUGAAGAUGAUCAUAAGAACCCGACGGUGACGCGCGAGCAGGUGGACUUCCAGCACCAUCAGCUGGCUGAGGCCUUCAAGCAAUACAACAUCUCCUGGGAGCUGGACGUGCUGGAGGUGAGCAACUCCUCCCUUCGCCGCCGCCUCAUCCUGGCCAACUGUGACAUCAGCAAGAUUGGGGAUGAGAACUGUGACCCCGAGUGCAACCACACGCUGACGGGCCACGACGGCGGGGAUUGCCGCCACCUGCGCCACCCUGCCUUCGUGAAGAAGCAGCACAACGGGGUGUGUGACAUGGACUGCAACUAUGAACGGUUCAACUUUGAUGGUGGAGAGUGCUGUGACCCUGAAAUCACCAAUGUCACUCAGACUUGCUUUGACCCCGACUCUCCACACAGAGCCUACUUGGAUGUUAAUGAGCUGAAGAACAUUCUUAAAUUGGAUGGAUCAACACAUCUCAAUAUUUUCUUUGCAAAAUCCUCAGAGGAGGAGUUGGCAGGAGUAGCAACUUGGCCAUGGGACAAGGAGGCCCUGAUGCACUUAGGUGGCAUUGUCUUGAACCCAUCUUUCUAUGGCAUGCCUGGGCACACCCACACCAUGAUCCAUGAGAUUGGUCACAGCCUGGGCCUCUAUCACGUCUUCCGAGGCAUCUCAGAAAUCCAGUCCUGCAGUGACCCCUGCAUGGAGACAGAGCCCUCCUUCGAGACUGGAGACCUCUGCAAUGAUACCAACCCAGCCCCUAAACACAAGUCCUGUGGUGACCCAGGGCCAGGAAAUGACACCUGUGGCUUUCAUAGCUUCUUCAACACUCCUUACAACAACUUCAUGAGCUAUGCAGAUGACGACUGUACGGACUCCUUCACGCCCAAUCAAGUCGCCAGAAUGCACUGUUACCUGGACCUGGUCUACCAGGGCUGGCAGCCCUCCAGGAAACCAGCGCCUGUUGCCCUCGCCCCCCAAGUUCUGGGCCACACAACGGACUCUGUGACACUGGAGUGGUUCCCACCUAUAGAUGGCCAUUUCUUUGAAAGAGAAUUGGGAUCAGCAUGUCAUCUUUGCCUGGAAGGGAGAAUCCUGGUGCAGUAUGCUUCCAACGCUUCCUCCCCAAUGCCCUGCAGCCCAUCAGGACACUGGAGCCCUCGUGAAGCAGAAGGUCAUCCUGAUGUUGAACAGCCCUGUAAGUCCAGUGUCCGCACCUGGAGCCCAAAUUCAGCUGUCAACCCACACACGGUUCCUCCAGCCUGCCCUGAGCCUCAAGGCUGCUACCUCGAGCUGGAGUUCCUCUACCCCUUGGUCCCUGAGUCUCUGACCAUUUGGGUGACCUUUGUCUCCACUGACUGGGACUCUAGUGGAGCUGUCAAUGACAUCAAACUGUUGGCUGUCAGUGGGAAGAACAUCUCCCUGGGUCCUCAGAAUGUCUUCUGUGAUGUCCCACUGACCAUCAGACUCUGGGACGUGGGCGAGGAGGUGUAUGGCAUCCAAAUCUACACGCUGGAUGAGCACCUGGAGAUCGAUGCUGCCAUGUUGACCUCCACUGCAGACACCCCACUCUGUCUACAGUGUAAGCCCCUGAAGUAUAAGGUGGUCCGGGACCCUCCUCUCCAGAUGGAUGUGGCCUCCAUCCUACAUCUCAAUAGGAAAUUCGUAGACAUGGAUCUAAAUCUUGGCAGUGUGUACCAGUAUUGGGUCAUAACUAUUUCAGGAACUGAAGAGAGUGAGCCAUCACCUGCUGUCACAUACAUCCAUGGAAGUGGGUACUGUGGCGAUGGCAUUAUACAAAAAGACCAAGGUGAACAAUGCGACGACAUGAAUAAGAUCAAUGGUGAUGGCUGCUCCCUUUUCUGCCGACAAGAAGUCUCCUUCAAUUGUAUUGAUGAACCCAGCCGGUGCUAUUUCCAUGAUGGUGAUGGGGUAUGUGAGGAGUUUGAACAAAAAACCAGCAUUAAGGACUGUGGUGUCUACACGCCCCAGGGAUUCCUGGAUCAGUGGGCAUCCAAUGCUUCAGUAUCUCAUCAAGACCAGCAAUGCCCAGGCUGGGUCAUCAUCGGACAGCCAGCAGCAUCCCAGGUGUGUCGAACCAAGGUGAUAGAUCUCAGUGAAGGCAUUUCCCAGCAUGCCUGGUACCCUUGCACCAUCAGCUACCCAUAUUCCCAGCUGGCUCAGACCACUUUUUGGCUCCGGGCGUAUUUUUCUCAACCAAUGGUUGCCGCAGCUGUCAUUGUCCACCUGGUGACGGAUGGGACAUAUUAUGGGGACCAAAAGCAGGAGACCAUCAGCGUGCAGCUGCUUGAUACCAAAGAUCAGAGCCACGAUCUAGGCCUCCAUGUCCUGAGCUGCAGGAACAAUCCCCUGAUUAUCCCUGUGGUCCAUGACCUCAGCCAGCCCUUCUACCACAGCCAGGCGGUACGUGUGAGCUUCAGUUCGCCCCUGGUCGCCAUCUCGGGGGUGGCCCUCCGUUCCUUCGACAACUUUGACCCCGUCACCCUGAGCAGCUGCCAGAGAGGGGAGACCUACAGCCCUGCCGAGCAGAGCUGCGUGCACUUCGCAUGUGAGAAAACUGACUGUCCAGAGCUGGCUGUGGAGAAUGCUUCUCUCAAUUGCUCCAGCAGCGACCGCUACCACGGUGCCCAGUGUACUGUGAGCUGCCGGACAGGCUACGUGCUCCAGAUACGGCGGGAUGAUGAGCUGAUCAAGAGCCAGACGGGACCCAGCGUCACAGUGACCUGUACAGAGGGCAAGUGGAAUAAGCAGGUGGCCUGUGAGCCAGUCGACUGCAGCAUCCCAGAUCACCAUCAAGUCUAUGCUGCCUCCUUCUCCUGCCCUGAGGGCACCACCUUUGGCAGUCAAUGUUCCUUCCAGUGCCGUCACCCUGCACAAUUGAAAGGCAACAACAGCCUCCUGACCUGCAUGGAGGAUGGGCUGUGGUCCUUCCCAGAGGCCCUGUGUGAGCUCAUGUGCCUCGCUCCACCCCCUGUGCCCAAUGCAGACCUCCAGACCGCCCGGUGCCGAGAGAAUAAGCACAAGGUGGGCUCCUUCUGCAAAUACAAAUGCAAGCCUGGAUACCAUGUGCCUGGAUCCUCUCGGAAGUCAAAGAAACGGGCCUUCAAGACUCAGUGUACCCAGGAUGGCAGCUGGCAGGAGGGAGCUUGUGUUCCUGUGACCUGUGACCCACCUCCACCAAAAUUCCAUGGGCUCUACCAGUGUACUAAUGGCUUCCAGUUCAACAGUGAGUGUAGGAUCAAGUGUGAAGACAGUGAUGCCUCCCAGGGACUUGGGAGCAAUGUCAUUCAUUGCCGGAAAGAUGGCACCUGGAACGGCUCCUUCCAUGUCUGCCAGGAGAUGCAAGGCCAGUGCUCGGUUCCAAACGAGCUCAACAGCAACCUCAAACUGCAGUGCCCUGAUGGCUAUGCCAUAGGGUCGGAGUGUGCCACCUCGUGCCUGGACCACAACAGCGAGUCCAUCAUCCUGCCAAUGAACGUGACCGUGCGUGACAUCCCCCACUGGCUGAACCCCACACGGGUAGAGAGAGUUGUCUGCACUGCUGGUCUCAAGUGGUAUCCUCACCCUGCUCUGAUUCACUGUGUCAAAGGCUGUGAGCCCUUCAUGGGAGACAAUUAUUGUGAUGCCAUCAACAACCGAGCCUUUUGCAACUAUGACGGUGGGGAUUGCUGCACCUCCACAGUGAAGACCAAAAAGGUCACCCCAUUCCCUAUGUCCUGUGAUCUACAAGGUGACUGUGCUUGUCGGGACCCCCAGGCCCAAGAACACAGCCGGAAAGACCUCCGGGGAUACAGCCAUGGCUAAGGAAGGACAAGAAGUUGUCAAAGAAUUCCCAACGCCAGGACCCACAUCCCUUUGGUAUUGAUUUCACAGUCAGCUGCUCAACGGAAUGGCCUCUCCACACCAGGGAUCCUUAGCACCCAACCGGUCUGCCUUUAAUUUUACCCAGGAAGGACUCACAUUGGGGCGAAUGAACCAAGUUUCGCCAUGCUGGAUGAUGAAAUGGAUUCCCAUCCCAAAGUCUGAGAUGGAUUGCAUAUACAGUGUGCAGUCCCAGAGCCUCCUAAAAUUCUAGCCAUUUGUCACACAACCACAGCAAGAAACGUGUUCUAUAUCUAGAGUGUGCCCAUCUGUGUUUAGUACACAUGCAUGCAUACACACCCAUACAAACAUCUGUGUGAGGGCAGUUCUGGAGAUGAGCAGAGAGAGACCGGAAUAAACUCAAUCUUUUCUUUCCCAAGCUCCUAGCCAACACUAUCCUUGGGAGAAAGAAAUUUGCAGAAACUGCUAAGACCAAGUGUGGAGAUGUCAAGCUAGUUCACACUCUGAGGCUCAGAAUAUGUAGGACAUGCACAAUUGUGCAGUCCUUUGGGAUUGGAAGUGAAACAGUCUGUGAUCCCCUACCUUCUAGGGAACUAGGACCUAGGAAGAGGUAAAGAUUAUCAGGUAUGCAAAGCGCCCCAAUUCUUCUGCUGCCAUGGGGGAUUUUACCCCAACUCCAGGGUUCGAGGCCAAUCUGAGAAUGGCUUAGGAUUGCAAUGUCAAGGUAUUAUAUCAGCCCCUUGCUUGAGGCUUGAGGUCAUAAUAUCCCUCUAGGACUUACCUGUUCCCCCAGAUCUUGCCUUGGGACCACAUUUGCUGCUACUUUUCCUGCUGCUCUAUCCUAUACAUUGAAUAAUCCAAGAUGGUAGAACUAGGUUAGGAAAAAUUCCACACAACCAAACAGUCUGCCUUAAAAGUGACCCACAUUUUUCCAUAGCUCCUCACUUUUUAGCCCUUCUGCAAGAGAAAAACCCUCAUGGGUCCACAUGGUGAGAAGUUAAGUUUCCUGUAAGUGGGCCUCUCACCCUGGAAAGGAGUUGAGGGACAUCAGAUGCUGGAACCCUCACUGAAAGUCCAGAAUGUCUAAGCCAGUGUUAGAUUUUGUAAACAAGUGGAACAGUGUUAAAUUUCUAUGAUGUUGGAGCCAUCCAGAGACUACUGGAAUUGUCGAGACUUUUGGAUUAUUAUCCUUAUCCUUAUCCUAAUCUUCCUAGCCCUUCAGGCUAGAGUAGGCUUUGAUCCUGAGAACCUUGCUGUUGCUCUGAGGAGAUAUAAUUCUGGGAGAAAGAAUCUUUUAUAAGAACAGUACAGAUUGUUCUCAAGAGGGCCAUCAGAAGGAAGCCAAAGAGUUCACAGCCUCAGCACCAACAACUCAACAUGGUCAUCAUGUUUUCUAUAUGGUUUUUCCAGCUAGCAGUACUCCCUUCCAUACCUGUGACUGGGCAGUGCUUUUCUCUCUCCCAUGUCUAGCCUCCAAAAGUUAAGUGAAAAUUAGUCAACUGCACGUGGAAGCCCCCACCACUUUGGGGAUCUCUUUAUUUCUUUUCAGCCAGGGACCUGUCCACUCCCUUUGAAUUAAUAUGGGAAGAAAUUAAUACAGGAUGAACUGGAGAGAAGGGUUGAGUGUGGCAUACUUUCUGAAACCUGGAGCUGGGAAUUGCGGAGAAGGGAAGGUCUAGACUAGUUACAUCACAUAGGGAUUACUGUAAAUCAAGUCAUCUCAAGUCUAGUGAAGACAGCCAACAGAAACAAAACCUAGCAUAGGGAUAGAAAAUACCAUGCACGUGUGCAGCCCCACCUAAUUCCUGCAUCCAAGGCAGGUGUUGUUAAUCUAUCAUAGCACUUAAAAAAAAAAAAAAAAAGAGACCAAAAAUAACUUUAGGAACCACCAUAUUAUAUCACUCCCAAUAGCACUGACCUGGUGAUCAAAAACACUUGAGAAGACAUCUAUUGGCCAUCUCUGGCCAAUUACACUAAGAAACAUAUCAAGGUGCUUUUGGCACAGGUGCCCACAAAUACGGAUGCAGUGCUGAGAUAGUUUAUGAGACUUGUACCAUUUCACAAACUCUGAAAUUGGGUUCCAUAUUGGCAAGGCUGCCACAGUUGUUAAGAAUAAUCCUCUAUGUUUCUUCCUCACAAAACCAUAUCUCAUUUAUAUCCAGACCAUUACUUCACUAUAAUUACAAGGACAAAUUAUUAGCAAGAAAUAAGAAUAGUAUUAGAAGAAUUGAUCCUAUUUUGAACCCCUCUCCAGUAUCUUCACACUCUUGUCAACUCUCCAGGCCUCUCUCUUGCCCUGAGUUAUCAGCCUGUGUGGUGUUAACUACCUUAGAAGGUACAAGCUAAGAAAUGUAACAGUAUCAACCCUCCCAGUUGCUUAAUUAUACCCAUAGGUAAUACAAAAAGCUCUGAAGACCCAAAGAUGACAUUACUAAUGAUGUGAUUUCAGGAGCCACAGAAGAACCUUACCAGCUUCCCUCAAAUCAGUCCUUAUCCUCUUUCUAUCUUCACUCCCAUCAUCAUCUAUUUUCACACUAUCCAGCUAAGCAAAGAUUCCUGGAGGCUGACUUGUAUCUUCAGACUCACAGAGUGAAUUCAGCUCUUCUGAAUCAAGACCCACCCAGUCUCUUUCAUUCAGACCUGUUGCUAACAAAUUUAUAUUUGCCAAGGAUAUUAGGCAAAAGAGGCUACUUGAUUGGUGGCCAACCUCGUGCCCACAUGGAAGGUAUCUUUAAUAGGGUCUUUUCAAACCUUAGUGGAGGAGGGUCAGCUCAAUUUGGGCAAUGCAUUUGUUCCCAGUUUCAUUUUCUUCCUGGGAAUUAACUCGUCAUUUCAUUCCUUCAGUCAUCUUCUGUGUAGGUGACCGGAGCACUGAGAGGCAGCUCUGAUGCACUAUUGUGUGUCAGCAGCUCAAAGGCCCUAAAACACUGAAGGUUCUGCAUCUGAAGUAUUAGAUUGUUAGCAGCAAAAUAUGAAAGAUGAGGUGGACAGUCCUCUAAGCCCUAUUUAGGGAAGCUUUUCCAAGCCACAAUCUUAACUACCUACCCAAAGGAUUUGCAUUACCCCCAGAUUCUGUGCCAACAACCUUUUAAGGAAAUACAGUCCUUGGGAAAUGAGUUUUGAUGGUGAAUUGGGGUGUUAAGGAAGGGAAAGAUUGUCAUAGAUGGUAGGGCUUUGAAAAUGCAGGGUAUCAGCUGCCACUCCUGGCUUCAACACAUUGAGUCACUGCCUAGACGGUUCUCUUGGUCUUAUUCCCAUCCUGGCCAAUGCUUAAAUACUAUUUGUUGAAAAUAAUUCUUUGAGACAGAUUUCAGCUACCUCCCUUCCAGGUUCGAUUUAACUUGGUUGUAAUUGUCAAUUUGUUGUUAUAGGUCUUACCUGUGUGAAAGAAAGAAAAAGAAAGAAAGAAAGAAAGAGAAAGGAAAUUAUAAGGUCAAGUUAACAGUUUUGAGGUUUUGUGUUUUUUUCUGGAACUACUUCAAGUGAGAAAAUAAAAAAAAAUGGUGACAAAGCUGUACAGAUAGAGAUAAUAGAAGACAAAGAGAUUAAAAGGAAAUAAAAAUGCAUGAUUAAAAACUAAGAAUAAAAAACCUAUUUUUAUGUUUCCUAAAGGAAAUUGUUUAUUCUACAGCCUCAGUAGGUAGACACAAACAUAAAGAUUUCCCUAGAAGACAUAGAGUGGGAUUUGAUAACACUGUCUGUUAUUUUCUGUACAUUGUGGUAGGUCCAGGAAAUAUGACAUUUUCCCCCUUGAUGUGUUAUUGUUGUUGUUGGGUGGGGUGGGCAUUUUGUUUAUUUGUUUGGUGGCAAUCAGUGGUAGUAGGGAGUGGGAGGGCUUAUAUUGGUUUUUCCAGCUAUUAAGGGGACAUAUUGUGUCGUUGUGCUUUUCACGUUAUAAAAUGUUUAUAUUUACCAGUACAGCACUGGGCUUUAUAAAGACUGCACUCAGAACCACACUGCACAGUCCAGUUUUUUAAAAAGCUGCUACAUGACAGACAGGUAAUCCCACUGAGUGAGUUUUGAGAAACAAAUCAAACGAAGUAAACAAGAAACAUAAAAACCAAAUAGCAAAUGAAUAAAAGCCUGUUCUUGUAACUUAUUCAACUUUUGCCAAAUUCCUACCAAUCACUUGCUUUUUAAAAGAAAUGUAUAAUAGCCAAAAGAGAAAUUAUGUCCCUGUUGUACAGAAGUUAGAAUUUUUGACUCCAGGCAGCAGUUUGCUCAGUGAUCUUGAACAAGUUAUCCAAUUGCCUCUACAUUUGCAUCAGUUUCUCUAGCUGCAAAAUGGGGAUAAUACUAUAUACCUACCUCACAGUGGGAGGGCAGGAGAUUUUGAGGCCCUGAGGUUUUAGGUGGGCUGUGAGGGCCAACGCUUGACACAAAGUCCAUGGGUUAUUAUUCAAGAAUGCACAGGCCCAUCGGCCUUUUAGAAAGACAAGACAGGGAGUGCUUGUUUGAUAUUUCAAGGAAUAAAGCCGGAGCUCCUGAAUUGUAGUCCACCUUAAAAGAGAGACCUGUAUUGGAGAAUAUUUUAUUUUUUUGGCAAAUUUGAUCUUACCCUUUACCAGUUCUAUAAUUUGGUUAAAAGCUGAUUAUGUCCUACAAUGUCAAAGUCAGCUAACUGUCGUCUACUUAAGACUUCUGGUCAUUUCCAACUUAUAGAGGAAGGGAGUCUCUAAAAUCUCUUCUUCAGAAGGCACCUCACUUCUCAGACUUAAAAUUCCACAUCAAGUGUUCCAUUAAAAGAAGAUAAGGCAUUCUGAGUGCAAACAAAUGGGGGCUUCUUAAACUACACACCAGCAGUCAGUGAGGAAAACUUUGAACAAUUAUUGAGUUGCUUUCUUGGGUCUCUAUAAUCAAUAACCUGUCUGCAGAUAUCUAUCUAUAUAAAGAUAUUAUAUAUAAAUAUAAAUUUACAUAUAUAUGCACAUGUAUAUAUAGUUGUACAUAUAUGUGUGUAUAUAUAUACUUAAAUGUAAUAUUUACAAAAUAAAACUGUGAUCUCGUCUAGAGAAAAUGUAUUCAUAUUACAAACUGCUCUUCCAUAUUUAUGUACCAUAUUAUACCUUUUUAUUAUUGUUAUAAUUAUUAUGGGUAUUUCUAAUUAAUAUGAUGUUGAAACCUGUUUGGCACCUUCUGGAAGCUACCAAAAAAAUGACACUCCAUUGAAGUGCUUAAAAGCUGUUCUCAUAAGAAUUCUUCUGGCCUAUUGUAAAAAAGAAAAAAAAAAAGAAAAAGAAGAAAGACACAAAGAAAAUAAUCUAAACACCAAAAACUAAACACAAUUCCAAUCCUUUUUCUGUACCUCACGCGCAUAAAUUUGCUGCUCCUAUUUUUUUUUCUGUUUAUGUGUUUUUAUGGAUCUAAGUUAAAUCUUUUGGCAAUAUAUAAAAAUGUAAAUAGUAAACUUUAUUUAUUAAGAAUGUCAUCUUUUUUAAUUUAUAUUUACACAAUUGUUCAUCUAAUUUAUUUUUUCUAUACAGUUUUAAAUACUCAGACAUAUUUUGCUGUUCAUGAUAUUUUUAUCCUGUUCUCAUGGAUUUGUUUUCCCAUACUGUUUUCUCUGAUCUCAAUUACAGGUUGGAUCUCACAAAUAAUAAUGUCAGAGACAGAAAUAUUUUGCCACUGUUGAUUACUAUACUUUAAAGUUCUAUAUUAUGAAAAUAUAUAAUAGCUUGUACGCUUCA